AUCCCUCUGCAGAGCCCGGGGUCACCAGGAGGAGACGCCAUGACCCCCACCCUCGCAGCCCUGCUCUGCCUAGGGCUGAGUCUGGGCCCCAGGACCCACGUGCAGGCAGGGCCCUUCCCCAAACCCACCCUCUGGGCUGAGCCAGGCUCUGUGAUCAGCUGGGGGAGCCCCGUGACCAUCUGGUGUCAGGGGAGCCUGGAGGCCCAGGAGUACCGACUGGAUAAAGAGGGAAGCCCAGAGCCCUGGGACAGAAAUAACCCACUGGAACCCAAGAACAAGGCCAGAUUCUCCAUCCCAUCCAUAACAGAGCACCAUGCGGGGAGAUACCGCUGCCACUAUUACAGCUCUGCAGGCUGGUCAGAGCCCAGCGACCCCCUGGAGCUGGUGAUGACAGGAGCCUAUAGCAAACCCACCCUCUCAGCCCUGCCCAGCCCUGUGGUGGCCUCAGGGGGGAAUAUGACCCUCCAAUGUGGCUCACAGAAGGGAUAUCACCAUUUUGUUCUGAUGAAGGAAGGAGAACACCAGCUCCCCCGGACCCUGGACUCACAGCAGCUCCACAGUGGGGGGUUCCAGGCCCUGUUCCCUGUGGGCCCCGUGAACCCCAGCCACAGGUGGAGGUUCACAUGCUAUUACUAUUAUAUGAACACCCCCCGGGUGUGGUCCCACCCCAGUGACCCCCUGGAGAUUCUGCCCUCAGGCGUGUCUAGGAAGCCCUCCCUCCUGACCCUGCAGGGCCCUGUCCUGGCCCCUGGGCAGAGCCUGACCCUCCAGUGUGGCUCUGAUGUCGGCUACGACAGAUUUGUUCUGUAUAAGGAGGGGGAACGUGACUUCCUCCAGCGCCCUGGCCAGCAGCCCCAGGCUGGGCUCUCCCAGGCCAACUUCACCCUGGGCCCUGUGAGCCCCUCCCACGGGGGCCAGUACAGGUGCUAUGGUGCACACAACCUCUCCUCCGAGUGGUCGGCCCCCAGCGACCCCCUGAACAUCCUGAUGGCAGGACAGAUCUAUGACACCGUCUCCCUGUCAGCACAGCCGGGCCCCACAGUGGCCUCAGGAGAGAACGUGACCCUGCUGUGUCAGUCAUGGUGGCAGUUUGACACUUUCCUUCUGACCAAAGAAGGGGCAGCCCAUCCCCCACUGCGUCUGAGAUCAAUGUACGGAGCUCAUAAGUACCAGGCUGAAUUCCCCAUGAGUCCUGUGACCUCAGCCCACGCGGGGACCUACAGGUGCUACGGCUCAUACAGCUCCAACCCCCACCUGCUGUCUUUCCCCAGUGAGCCCCUGGAACUCAUGGUCUCAGGACACUCUGGAGGCUCCAGCCUCCCACCCACAGGGCCGCCCUCCACACCUGCCUCACACGCCAAGGAUUACACAGUGGAGAAUCUCAUCCGCAUGGGCAUGGCAGGCUUGGUCCUGCUGUUCCUCGGGAUUCUGUUAUUUGAGGCUCAGCACAGCCAGAGAAACCCCCAAGAUGCAGCCGGGAGGUGAACAGCGGAGAGGACAAUGCACCCUUCAGCGUGGUGGAGCCUCAGGGACAGAUCUGAUGAUCCCAGAAGGCUCUGGAGGACAAUCUAGGACGUCCAGAGGGGGGUGAGAUUUCAGGCCACACACUGUGGAAGGUAAUCAUGUCUGAUCACAAAUUUUGGGUCUCCACCUUACUUCCAAUCUAUGUUGUGAAUGCCCAGUUGAGACCCACGGAAAAGAGCUCAUGGGUGAGUGUGAAGUGCUUCUCUGUCUUAAGUUCCCAGAGAUCCUUGCCUCUUGGAGGCCAGCAAACACUAACUCUUGAGGAAUUCGGCCGGGCGCGGUGGCUCACGCCUAUAAUCUCAGCACUUUGGGAGGCUGAUGCGGGCGGAUCAUGAGGUCAGGAGAUCGAGACCAUCCUGGCUAACACGGUGAAACCCCGUCUCUACUAAAAAUACAAAAAAAUUAGCCGGGCGUGGUGGCGAGUGCCUAUAGUCCCAGCUACUCAGGAGGCUGAGGCAGGAGAAU